AUUUUCUCUUUAUCAUUGUUUGAUUAUUGUAUAAGUAUUAUGAUUGGCAUUUUGCAAUUUGAGCAGAGCUGAUAUUAUAUAUGGUAUUUCUAAGUACUUUUUUUUUUGACUCUGCCAAACUGUUAAGUCAUUCUCCAUCCAUCUAUCCAUCCAUCCACCCAUCCAUCCAUCCUCUUCUCAUUUUGACUUCUAUUAGUUAUUUCCUGAAGCCCGUAUAUCACUGAGAAAAAGUUAAUCUUAAGUGAAUAACUUAGGUCAAAAUGAGAGGAGAAUGAAGAAUUAAGUGAAUGUAGGCAGAGUCAGAAAAAAAAAUAGUGUCUCUCUUUAAAGCAUUACUUUUUUUGGUGAUGCCUUUGAAGGAAGUGAAAUUGGUGUAUGAUCUAAUGCUACAAAACCAUAUCUUGCUCUCAUAGAUUUUAAGAUUUCUCUUUUGAAUGAUCCAUUGCUGUCCUUUCUUUACACGUAUCUUUUCUCCCUAUCUUCCUUGUUAAAUACAUUUUUUCGUUAUAUACUUUUGAAGCAAGUCUUGAUUUUUUUGUAUUUUCCCCAUUUUUCUUCAAAUGUUCCACAGUUCCCUAAAAUAAGAUAGCAUUUUUGUCUUUUUCUACAGUCUAUUCUUUGCUGUUUACUUCAUCCCCACCCACCGCCACCAAAAAUGCCUUCAGAAAGUCCCUACCUUUUCUUGUACAUUGUCCUUCUGUUCAGAUUCUUGUAUCGCUGAUACUCUCCCCUGCUACCCAUUCUCCUCCCAACAGUUUUCUUUGAUAGUGAUAUCUGCCUUGGAAUUUCCACUGUGCCUGUUAAACUCUUUGAGAAGGAUAAUUCUGUCAACGUUUACUUCUCUUCCCCUUCUAGCCCCAAAGACUGAGGACAGUGUCCUCCUCAUGCAUUCCUGUGACGAGGAAUCUGCACUGAGGUUUCUACUCUUUCCCUUACCAGGAUUCUGAAUUGUCUGUGACUGUCUGAUAUGAUUGCUGAUCUCUUUCCUGUUCUCAGAUAGGACACAAGGGGUUCCAUUCGGAGUUGGCUCAGGACAUUCAGAUGCCAUUAUUUUAGUAAUGAUCACAUGAUGUUUUGAGGGCAGCCUGAAAAAAAUAGAGUCUCUAACAGAGGAGCUGGGUAAAAUCAGAGUAGGACCAUCUCUAAUGCCUUUUCUAGCUCUCUUACUCUGAUUUUGUGAAUUUAUCCUUAGGGACAGUUUUUCAUCAGGAUGAGACCCUGCUGUGGUCUGAAUGUUUGUGUCUCUCUCCCCUCACCAAAUUUAUUUAUAUGUUGAAAUCUAACCCCCAAGUUGAUGGUGUUAAGAGGUGGGGCCUUUAGGAGACAGUUACAUCAUGAGGGUGGAUCCCUCAUGAAUGGCAUUCACGCCCUUAUAAAAGAAGCUUAAGGGCCAGGUGUGGUGGUGCGAAUCUAUAGUUCCAGCUAUAUGGAAGGCUGUGGCCGUGAGAAGAUUGCUUGAGGCCAGGAGUUUGAGGCUGCAGUGAGUGAAUAACCCCUGCACUCCAGCCUGGACAACAUAGCAAGACUCUCUCUUAAAAUAGAUAGAUAGAUUAGAUAGACAGCCUAAGGGAGCCUGAUUGCCCCUCCACCAUGUGAGGACACAGCAAGAAGGCACCAUCUGUGAACCAGGAAAGGAGCCCUCACCAGACAUCUGAUUUGUUGGUGCCUUGAUUUUGGACUUACCAACCCCGAGAACUGUAAGAAAUGAAUUUCUGUUGUUUGUAAUUACCCAGGCUAAGGUAUUUUGUUAAAGCAGACCAGAUGGACUAAGUCAGCCCCAUAAUGACCCGUUUUAUAUUUUUAUUUAUAAUCUAUCUGCUGCUUAAUUUUGUGAUUAGUGGCCAGCUACUGUUUACUCAUCUUUUAUUCAUCUGUAAAACUCUUUUUAACUUGUCUUUGUAAGAAACGGUUGGCUAACAGAUGAAUUUUCAGGUUGUUCAGUUUUAAAAUGUUUUACUUAAAAGGGUAAGACAACUCCCCAAUGCAAAGUGUGACUUCAGAGAUAACUUUCAUUUCUUUGAAAUGUAGGAAGUCCAUAGCCAUUGCUGGCUGACAUCUUUCUGCUCAAUAUGCUCCAGGGGAAGAUUAUCAAAUUUUAGCUUCUGAGCUUUCAAAUGGCUCUUAUUAUCAGUGGCAUAUUACAUGAAACUGGUUUUGGGCUCUUCAAAUUUAUAUUUUUGGCAAAGGUGUUGGGAGAUUUGAUUUCAUUCGUCAUCACUGCAGUACCUGGCGCAUAGUAGGCUCUCCAUUUGGUGUGUUGGAUGAAUGAAGAAAGUGAUUCUGCUAGUCAGUGGGGUUUAAAAACAAGUGUCCACCAACUUAAUGGGUCCCCAUUGAUCCUGAGUUCACCUCUGUUGCCCUGUAUAUAUGUGACCCCAUGUUUAUUGCAACCUUAUGGGCAUCUCAGGCACUGCAGAGAACAGCCUCUUAAAAUUUCUGGUAGAGGCCUGGUGCGGUGGCUCACGCCUGUAAUCCCAGCACUUUGGGAGUCUGAGGCGGACGGAUCAUGAGGUCAGGAGUUCGAGACCAGCCUGACCAACAUGGUGAAACCCCAUCUCUACUAAAAAUAUAAAAAUUAGCCGGGCAUGGUGGCAUGCACCUGUAGUCCCAGCUACUCAGGAGUCUGAGGCAGGAGAAUUGCUUGAACCUGGGAGGCGGAGGUUGCAGUGAGCUGAGAUCGUGCCACUGCACUCCAGCCUGGGUGACAGAGCUAGACUCCGACUCAAAAGAAAAAAAAUUUUUGGUAGACUCCUAUGUGCCAUUUCUGGAGAACUGAAAUAGUAGUGGACAUACAUAGGAUUCAUUUUAGUGUAGAUAUGACUUUUUAGUGAAACUUGAAGUCCUACUUCCUGUGUGUGAAAUAGGGUAAUAGGAUCACACCCGAAGAAAUGCCGCCUUGUUCAAAAGUGACAGGAUCGCUGUUCAGUUUGGAAUAUUGGAAAGUGGGCAGGUUUAUUUGGAAGCACUUUGUUUUUACUAUAUGUGUAAAACUCCAGGGAGCAUUGAAUAGGAUAUGAGGUGCUCCCUUUGGCUGUGCAUUAGCAACGUGGCAGUUACUGAUCUGUCAUUUACUUUGAAAAGGAAUUACAAAGUUUUGGCCUCAUGCCUGGAGUAGCUCCAGAUGGUCAGAAAAGAUUUUUGUACUGAAGUCAGAAAGUAUAUUGCAGUGAUAGAAUUGGGCUUGUCAUGUUUAUAUUAGAACACUGGCUUCCCACUUUAUUCCUCUGCAAAGUUUUUCUUUCUUUCUUUUUUCCCAGAGAGUGAGGGGAGGAAAUUGUUGCUUUAGAGUUAUGAGUCUAAUAUUUGGAAUACUGUUGUUCUUGGUGAUAAUGAUGUAGAGGUAUGAUUAUGUGGUUAAUGUAGUUACUUUGUCAACCUAAAUACCCCUGAUUCUUAGUAUUUACAAAGGAUGCAUGAAGGCUUGGAAUGUAGAGAUACACCAAGACCAUUGUAGCUGAUGUAGAAAUGCAGGUAAGAAGCUUCAUUUGGGUUGCGUUUGCUUGUCUGAUAACCUGGCUGUUAGCCCACAACUGUUAUUUAGUAGCUUACCAAACUUCAUCUGUUCUGUCUUCCCAUGAUUCUGUGGUUGCUAGGGGUAAUGAUGACGUUUGGGUGUUCAAUAUGGGUGGGAGGUGGGCCUGGGGAGAUGAGCAGUGAGGCGAUAAUGAUACUAACACCAAGUUUUGCCAUUUUAGGCAUUAGAGCAUCUUAAAUUCCACAUAUGAUCUUGUGUACCUUCAUAUCAACCCUGGAAGGGGAACGAUGUGAUUCCUAUUUUCCUGAUGAGAAAACUGAGACUUUGGGAGGUAAUAUCUGCCCAAGGCAAUAUCUAGGUAACUCCCUUCUGCAGCCUGUUUACAUAUAGUUUUGGCGAAAAUGACUACAAUUUCCUGUCCUUUCAGGACAGAGGUGGCUACAGGCUUCAGGAAAUAAAGCUCAUUUUCCUCUGGGAAACUCAGGACUUGUCUGGGUUGAGCCAUUUAGUAAAGCUUGGUCACAAGGCUCAGAUUAAGACCUGGAUCUACGUGCUGCUGUUCCCAGACUGCUUUCAGUUACUCUUGUGGUUACUGAGUAACUUGGGAGUUAGAAGAACAUUAACAAAGUUUUGUGUUUUCGAAGAAAAUGCUACACAUGGAGAAGUGACACUAAGUUGCAUACUUCAGAAAGGAAUUUUUAUCUGUUUUGAGAUUCUGGUCUAUACAUUGAAAAUGAACUAAUUUUGAUUAUUAUACUUUUAAUUGGUUGCACGAGUGUGUGAACAUAGGCAGCUCUUUUGAAGCACUUUUACUGAAAAGUGUAAAAAUUUUUGUUGCUGUUGUUCAGUAGCAGACAUAUACAAUACUCUCUUUUUGAGACAUACACAAUAUUCUCUUAUUGUGGAUUUAGGGGUCUUGUACCAGAUCACCCUUUUCUCAGAUUGCAGCUCUUCCUCCUUGCUUUAUGUAGAGUGGUUUCUAACUUGGUUCUUUCUCCUGUGCAGAUAUAAGACUUGGUCCGCAGUCUCCUACCCUCACCCAGUCUUCCAUGAGCUAUCAAAAUCCUCCUCUAGGCUUUUAUUAUUUUGCUUCCUAAUUUUGUCCUUUUAAAUUUCCACUGUUUAGAUAUUAUUCAGACAGCAGUGGUAUUUUUCUGUAUAUAAUGUGGCGCUGUAAUUAGUUUGAGUUCUUUUGGGGUUGUGUCUUAAACAGCGAGAAUGGCCUGAUUGAUGUGCUUUUUGAAGUCUUACUACCUUUUUGAUGAGAAGGAUGAAAGUGGUGUGGAGAUGAGUUUGUCUGGCUUACUGUAAAUCUGAUCUGUGAGGCUUUUCUGCGUUCACUAAGGCACCAGAGUCGGACUCUGCUUUUUUUCUUGUUUGAUGUUACUUUAUUACACUUAUGAAUGAAAUACUAAUGCUGUUAUUUUAUAGAAGAUCAUAAAAUAAAAGUACACUUUCUUAGUGUUUUAUGUUUCUUUAAAAAGAUAAUUACCGUGAGUCAUAGAGCUACAAUUACAUCAAGAGUUUCCUAUACGAAGCAAAGUCUCUGGUGGGUUUUUGGUACAGUCUUUGCACCUGGAUCAGUGGAGCAAAAUGUCAUCACACUUGAAAAAAAAAUUACUUAACAGGCCCAUUAAGAAUCUUCAGAAGUUUGCAUCUUGUUAGGGAUUUGUGGUCCAAGAGUUAGUACUACAGAACAGGCUCUUUUGUAGACCUAGGGAAACCAGUUUGUUUCUCUGCCACUUAACCUGCAAGACUUAUUAUAGGUGUUUCCUUCUCCUGUCUGUUUUGAAGAGACUUCCUCUGGGAAUUAAUGGUAGAAUACUUAUGACUCCUGAGAGCAGAGAACGUUCAGGCCAUCAUCAUCUUCUCCCUCUGGGCUGUACAUGGCCUCCCUGUGUCUCUACUGCCUGUCAUACCUCCCCACUCCUCCACCUCAGUCACAGGGCGACUGCCUUGCUUUCGGUCUACCUUUCCCAACUCUUCAGGCUCAUCCUGGUGGAUCCCAUUCUGUAGCCCCUGCUGCUCUUUUCAGGGGAUUCUAUUUUGUCUUAUACACUUUUGUCAUUUAGUUACCCACCUAUUCCCCCCAGUGGACUCCCAUUCUGGGCUCCUGCAGAGGGCUUGUAAGUUCACCUUUAUAUCCCCAGGGUCAGAGCUGAUGCUCUGCCGAGUGAAUGGGGAAGCGCCAGAAAGAACAGAAGCUAAUGAUGGACUGGCUCGACCAUGGCUCCCACUUUCAAUACUCAUCCCUCUGUUUCCUCAGACAUUUUACUUGAAUUAAUUUUGUAGUUCUCCUUCUGAACUGCUGAGCAAGUAUUUGGACACUUUGUGAGGAGCCUUUUUUUUUUUUUUUUUUGAGAUGGGGUCUCACUCUGUCUCCCAGGCUGGAGUGCAGUGGCACAAUCUCGUCUCACUGCAGCCUCCGCCACCCGGGUUCAAGCAAUUCUCCUGCCUCAGCCUGCUGAGUGGCUGGGAUCACAGGCUUAAGCCACCACGCUCUGGUAAUUGUUUGUAUUUUUGGAAGAGAUGGGGUUCCACCAUGUUGGCUAGGCUAGUCUCAAACUCCUGACGUCAGAUGAUCCACCUGCCUCGGCCUCCCAAAAUGCUGGGAUUACAGGCAUGAGCCACCGUGCCCGGCCAGAGGAGCCCUCAUUUAUAGCAAGAAUAAAAACAUUUUGUCAGGAAAUUUAAUAAUAAGCCCAGACUGAGUGCUUGCUAUGUGCCAGACACUGUUCUAAAUGCUUUACAUGCAUUUCUUCAUUUAAUCCUCACAGUGUCCUGAAUUAGGUGCUUUAUUUUAUUAUUUCCACUUUGCCAGUGAAGAAGCAGAGGUAGUGAGAGGGUAAGCAACUUGCCUGAAGUUAAAAGCUAGUCAGUUGUGGACUUAGGGUUUGUAGCCAGGCAGUUGUGGUCUUCAGGGAGGGGACAUAACAUCAUUCCCCUCCUGAAACUCCAUAUUCCUUUGUAAAUCUUAUUCUGUGUUACAUAUUUUCCUGUCCUUCAUUUAGUUAUUUAGGUCAGCUUCUUGUACUUCUGCUGCAAAACGUUGCUGUCAAUUUACUUGACCUGGUAACCUCCCGGUGAGUUUCGCCAGGGCUUCCAGUCAAUUUAGCAGGUCACUCUAGUACCUGUGGGAGGGUGAGGGCAUGGAAUCCUCAGGAGAGGGCUCUGCUGUUGGCUGCUGUCUCCACUUGAAGUGGACAGUUUUGAAUAUCUUAAUAAAAUCAAAUCGGAUGUUCUUAGGUAUUCAUUCAUUUUAUUUUCCUAAGCAAAAUGUUUUGUAAAAUGCUGCUUUUACGUGGCUAGAGCCACUAAAUAUCUCUAUUAAUACUUUUAGGCAAAGGUUGAGAUCUUUGAAGAAUUAGUGGGUUUUAAAAAUUUACUUAUUUUUAUUUUUUAAUUUUAAGUUCUGGGAUACAUGUACAGAACGUGUGGGUUUGUUACAUAGGUGAAUGAGUGGGUUUUUUAAGUUGUUUUUGCGUGCCUUUAGUCUUACUGGUUUGCCUUAGUUUCUCUACUCUCCAGACUGCUGUGCUGACUUUUCAUAGCUAUCUGACUUUUCAGUCCAGUGCCCUUUUGAUGCUCUGGCCAGGUGGCUCUUGUUUCAGCUUCACUGGGAGGGAGUUGUGGAAUCUGGCUGACAAUCCCAUUUAGUCUUCUUCAAUUUAAUUGGCCUUUUCCCCUUUCAGAUUCCAAGUAGGGGAAUAGCCUAAAGCCAUUUUAGGGGGGCUACUAAAGCAGUUUACAAGGUGAUGCCUUAUAUUUAAAUACCACCGUAUUUCCAAAUCUGUUUCUAUUAUAUAUAUCGUUUAUUGUAGCAUUCUCACAGUGACCCUGUGGUGUGAACACAGUGACUAUUAUCCCAGUUUUCAGAUGAGAAAACCUAGUCUGAGAGUUGUGUGCCUUUCCUUACUUAGGGCACUGUGGCAAAUAAAGGGAGAAGUCAAGCUACUGCUUCCAUUCCAGUCUCUGAAUUCCAGGUCCCCUGCUCCCUUUUCUUUCCAGGGCAUGUAUGAUGUCUCAAGGUUGGCUAACCUCUAAUUGAAAAUCUGUAGGUGCUUAUCUUCUGCACUUUUGAAAUGAUAUGAACGUGAAAUAUUUUCAACAUGCUAACAUUUUUCCAGGCCGUUAUUAGGGGAUUAAAUCAUCCUGUUACCGUAACUGCAAUUUUAGAUGUUCUGGUGCUAAACUGAGAUCUGUCAAUAGAGUGCAACCUUUCGAAAGUCUUAAAAAAUAGGGUACAUCUUGGACUCAAGAAUUAUGAUAUCAAAAUAAGACCCUUGGCUAUUUCCGGAGUGUGUUAGCCAAUCUACCCUGUGGUUUUCUUUCUCUGGAAUUGGUGAAGAAAGAGAUAAACAAGAUCCAAAACCAGGUCGCAUGAAAGGAUCAACACUCCCCUGGACAUACAGUUGUUUGGGAUAAUCGUAAAUCCUGCUGUCUGUAGUGGCUGACGAGGGGAGAAGAGCAGAAUCCUAGCACUCCGGCUACUGACUGUGAAACUAAUGUAUCUUUGCUAUCACAUAUUUAGCAUUUACCUUUUACUUUAAGCCAAAAACACCUUACACUUUUCUUAGAUGAGCUUUUUAAAAACAUUGUAAUUUAUGAAAAAAAUUUGAACAUAGACAAAAGUAGAGAAUAGUAGUGGAUCCCCCUGGACUUAUUACCCAGCCUUGACAAUCAAUCAGCUCGUGCCAGUCUUGUUUCAUCUUUACCCGUUUUCAUUCUCUGCUCCUUGCUGUAAUAUUCUGAAGCAAAUCUCAGGCAUAUUAUUUCAUCCUUCAAUAUUUCAGUAUUUUUUUCAGAUAAGUUCUUUCGGAAAUAUAUUUUCAUCUAAUUUAAAACAAAAAGUUUUCAGGAAAAAUACAGGCAUUUUUGCUGCAAAAAUUGGUCAGGAUUAUGCAAUUUCUAACUAAUCAGCAUUUUUCAAGGUUACUGGUUUUGGCUGACAAAAUUUUUUUUCUUAUAUGUGGAAAAAAUUAUUCACAGUAACAAAUGCGUGUUUUGAUAGUGCUAAAAAUUAGUCUAUUUUUCAGACUUAAUUAUUCAAUUAAAAAAUAAGACACUUCAUAAACUUUAAAACUAUUGUGUAGAAACACACUGUUCUUCAGUUUUAUGUGUUUUCAGUCAUUAUAUUUCCCAGCUAUUUCAAAUAGGCUAAAUAUAGUAUACCCUAAGCUUACUCAAUCGUUAGUUUAGACUCAACUAAUUUGGAAUUUUCAUUGAGUUGGAUAUAACUUUAAUAGCAGGUUUCCAUUCAAGCAAAGUAUUUGCUAAUUGCAGGUGAUUAUUAAGGCAAAGUCUUAAGGAUUUAUAGAAUAAGUAAAUGGUUUUAUGGGCUCAUGGAUCUUUAGGUAUAUAUAUAUUUAUACACCUUAAUGGUAUGAAUUUAGCCUGACUUGGAAAAACUAACCUGGUUUAUAUGUGUAUAUAGUCCAUUAAUUGAUUCACUAAAAUUUUUAUUUUGUUAAAAAUAGUGAAAUAAAAUCAGAAUUAAUUUUUUUUUAUUCUCUGUGAAGAGUCUUAUGAAAGGUGGUCAGAUUUAUAAGUCAGAUUGUGGCUAGUGAAUCUUAGUUUUUCUCUCAAAUACCUCAAGACAGCAUGGAGGCUGGUUGUCACACACAUUCAAAGGAACAAAAUACUUAUUAGCUAAAAAAGGGUAUGCACAUUUUUGGGGGCUUUGAAGCAUAUUGUAGGGCUUAGUAAUAAUGACAGUGAAAAUUAACAUAGCGAGCACUUCCGUAUGAAGUCAUUUUCUCAUUACCAUGGUCUUACGAGGAUAGAUGUUGUAUUUAUCCUUGUUUUACAGAUAGAAACUGAGACAUGGAGAGUGAAGUAACUGGCUCCAAUCCCAGUGCUAAGUGGUCAAGCCAGGGUCAGAAUUGUAACAGUUGAGUUCAUGAGUACUGGCCCUUAACAACUCUGCUGGAGUGCCUCCUUUGGUUAAAUACUAGUAGUUCAUAUGUCGGAAACUCAUCCUUCAUUUUCUUCAAUGAAAAUACGGCAUUUUACAGCAGUGCUGUCCAAUAGAAUUGUUGAAAUUAUGGAAAUACCCGCGUUAUCUAGUAUGCGUAUGCCCAUUAGUCACAUGUGGCUGUUGAUUACUCAAAUGUGGCUAGUGUGACUGAGAAAUAGAAUUCAAGGUUUUAUUUAAUUUUAAGUAAUUUAAAUUUAAAUAGUUACAUGUAGCUAGUGGUUCUAGUACUGGACAGAGAGGCUAUAGAGUUUGAGAGACCUGGGAGAAUUUGUAGUUUGCGUUUCCUGGGGUAAUGACAAUAUCUUGGCAUUUUGUGGCUAUCAGUAUCUUGACCUCGUUAGGGUUGUCAGUGAAUGGUUGUGUCAUGAAAUAGUAAUAAUGUUAAUAAAGGUGAAAUUUUUACAAAGUGGAUAAUUGAAUGUUUAAAACUGUGAUGCCUAACAACAAAAUCCUGUUUGAUCACCAACCUGGGAAAUCCACAGUCUACCGCAUCUGGAGGCAUCCUCUUGUUAAUUCCUUUGUAGCCAAGCAAAAACUGCUUUGACAUUCCCGCAUGAUUUUCAGCCUUGUAGAUGAGUUCUUGCUUUGUAAAGAGUCCAGCUUCUUGGUCAAGCUUAACAUUAGGCGUGAUGAUAAGAUAGUAAAAUGGACUUUGUGGGCCAAAAGCAGCCAUUAAGAAGCAAGUGUUUAACUCUUUAUCUUUCUCCUACAGCCUGAUGUUGACAGAGCUCCCAUCUAUGAAAAUACAUCAAGAAAACUCAGUGGUAAUGAAGCUAGAUUUCAUUUCAAAUGACACUGAGGCCACAUAAACGGUGACACUGAUGCCUCUUAUGAUGUGCUUUCAUCUAAGCCUUUAUGUGGCACUUAAGUCUAAUUAUUUUAAUUUUUUCUUUGUGUUGAUGAAAAGGGCCGGAGUAGUUGUUUCCACCAGCCAUGGUGGGGCUCUGAAAUGGAAGCAAGCAAAGCCUCCAGAUGGUGGCAGGUAUUGGACCAUAGCCACCCUGCAGACAUAAUUAAACAUGUCUGCAGCCCUCUCAUUUAGCAGUUAUAACACAGACAUUUUCUUUGUUGAUGGGAUUGAACUGUUAUUGUUAGCAUUUAUGUGAAGGACUUGCAGUACUAUAGCCAGGUGCUAUUUCUCAGCUACUGUGUUAAACACUGGGCCUGGAACUCUGCUUUGAAAGGUUUGGAGAGAAGGUUCCUCCCAACAUUGGGAAUGAACAUGGUGGUUGGGGUGUUUUCAGCAGGUCCUGUUUGCCCACUUUCCAUUUGUAAUUCUCAAGUGUAACAGUUCGAAUGUAGAGACUGGCUGUGAAAGUGGAUUGGGAUUUUAAGACAAAAAGUAUUGGACAGCAGGUGAAACACACUUCGUUCCUGGCUGCAGUACCAGCUUCUGUCUGAAGUUAGGUAAAUCAUUUAGUUGCUGUGGACUUUGACUUUCUUCAGUUGGCAAAACAACCUUUGGGAGGGGAAACCAAAUAUCACUAGAAAGUGAUUUGACUUCUCGAAAAGACAAUUAUGGUUUAUUUGUGAAAUAAAAGGUAGUUGUGAUGAGUGAGUUCCCGUUUGCUGUAUCUGCCUCCUUGCCAAUAAACUUCCCAUUUACACUUUUAAUGAUGAUUCAAAGAGCAGAUCAGCAUUAUGUAAAGGCAUUUUUGAUGAAUUAGUCUUAUGCAUGUCCCUAUAUGGUAUAUUCUGUAGUUAACUGUUUUCAUUGAACCUUUACAACUGACUCCACCUUACAAUGGGUGCAUGAUUUUGUAGCGUAAGUUUACUACCUGACCUUGUUUCAUGUCCUCUUCACUGAGGACAAAAAAAAAAAAAGUAACACUUUUCUCUUGUGCUUUUUCUCCCCUGAUCCCUUCCCCCACCACAUGACCCUUAAGAAAUGUUGUCCUUUUGGAAGCCAGGUCAUUUGUCUGAAUUUAGGAGAAUGUUGAGUUGCAUCUUCAAGAAAGGGAUGCAACACAGGAUGAGGACUGUGGAGGAAGACUUUCUCUGAGUAAGACCUUGCAAAACAUAGAUUGAAAUAUAAUUGUCUGCAAAUGAAUUGACAAGUGUUGGACCCCAUUUUUCCAGGCACUUGAUUGAAAGGCUGCUUCUAGCCUGAGGGAGGUCUUGAUGAUGCUACAUUAUUGCCUGUGGCCAUUGUGAGUGCCACUGAGGUGGCCCUCUUGUGUGCAAGUAGUUGUGGUUCCACAAUUCCGCUAGGCUAGUAUUCAGACCUAAUUCUCUGCUUACAGAUGCUGUGAAUUCCGUAACUCAGAAAUGUGUGCUCACAAACAUCAAAUCAGCCUGUACACAGAUACAUAGAGCAGCCAUGUAUCAAGGACUUAGAAUGACUGCUGAUCCUUGAACUCUUUUUUAAAAAGGAAAAAUUAGCACAAGGUUAAAACUUAAAGACAUCAGAUUAGUUCUGUUUAACAGCAACCUGUUACUUCGUGCUUUUGCAUGUCAGCAGCUUGUCCUAGAGUCAGCGAGAUUUCUUGCUUGUGACUUAAAGAAUCUUGUCUUUUGGCUGUAGAGUAUGAUUUCAUGGUGGAGGAUGUUGCAGAUAUCUUAGUUUGCUAUUUUAUAGCAUGGGUUAUACUUUAAGGGCUGAAAAAAAUAAGGUAAUUUAAGCCUGUUUUGAGACACACGGAAAGGAAGCUAUUUCAUAACUAUCAGUCAUGUGAAAUUUGGCAGGCCCCUAGCCCGUUAGUGGCCACAGUCACAUGAUUGAUUACCGGUUGGGGACCCACAGUUAGCUUAUUGCAGAACUGCAUCUGGCAUAAUUGGUGUUGUCAUCCAGUGUCAAACUAUCCACCCUGUUCUGCCAACUUCCUUCCAAUAACAAAACUUUCUUGCCUUGCACGAGUGAAAGCCUGUGUGAUUGUAUGUGUUUAGAAUUACAGAGUUUUAAACAUGAUCCAAUCACAACUAUUUGAACUUCUUGAUUUUAGUACAUUUGUACCUAUGUUGCCAAAAACAUUUUUUUCCUUGUCUUUGUGUCUUCUAAAACAUUGAAGGAAGAGGUCUUUGAUGCUUCCUUAAUACUUUUAUCAUGUUUGAAGUCCUGAGCUCUAUAAAUAAUAUAGUCCUUAUUAUCUUUUUAUCUUGAUAAUUUAUAAAACUGACUGUCCAAAGAUAUGUACGAUACUUGUAGUUUUAUAUCAAAGAAUUUUAAAUGCCAAGAACCAGGGAAGCCAUCUAAUUCUCCAUUCGAGCUAGUGCCGAGACCUACUGGACAACAUCUUGACACUUGGUCAUUGGCCUGUGCUGGAGGCAUGAUAUUCUAGUCCUGGUUCUGCCUCUGCCCGCCAGUUUGGUUUUAGAUCUCUUCAUUUUUGUGAUUAAUGAUAUGAAAAAGUUGGACCAAGUGGUCACUUAGGUUUCCUUCAGUUUUUGAUUUCUGUAUGAAGAUAUAGAAAUAUCCCCUACACGUCAACAACAACAAAAAUGGGAAUUAACCGAUUCCUUCUAAAAGCUGAAGGCUCCUUGGCAGUGGAUAUUGACCCUUCAACUUUUAGAAGGAAUCAGUUAAUUUUUUGUUGUUGAAACAUGUCUCAUUUUUAUAUUGAGCCUAAAUUGGCAUGGUCAGAGAUAGGCUUCUAUAGCACUAUUUUUCCACAUAUUUUUGAGUGGGGCACACAUUGAGAAACAUAUUUUACAUUGUAGCCCAGUAAACACACACACACACACACACACACACACACACACACACACACAAACAUUUAUAUACAUAUAACUGAAUCAAAAGUUUCACAAAUCAAUACUUGCCUUUUUCCUUUGUGAUGCAAUUCUAUUCGAUUUUAUUUAAAAGAAUGCCAGUCAGUGACCCACUAAAUUGAUUAUGUGACCCAAGAAUGGGUCCUGACCUGGAGUUCAAAAAACACUACUCCAUAGCAACCCAGAACACAUUCGUUUCUUCUUUCACAUGAUAACCCUGUAAACUCAACUAUGGUUAGCUUGUUUGCCUUUAGUCCUCUUUUACAGGCUUAAGGUCCCAGUUUCCAAAGCUUUUUCUUUCGUGAUUUGAUAUUUUGACUCAUCACCAUACUGGUCGGUUGUUCCUGGAUACUUACGGUUUGUAUCCCUCUUAAGGUACCAGAAGAAAUCUAAUCUCAAAAUAAAAUUUAACUAGGGCCAGGGUCUUUCUUUUAUAUUGUUUCCUACUAAUGUCAUUAUAUUACACAUUUAUUCUACAAAUGUUUGUUCUAUACAUGUGUACUGAGCACUACUAUGUGUUAGGGCUAUCCUUGGUGCUUGAGGACACUGCAGUGAGCAAAACAAAAAUGUCUGCAUUCAGAGAGUGUACAUUGUAGAGAAUUGCACUAGCCACUAGGAGUAUGGCAAUGUCAAAUGAAAUACCCAAGCGCUCAGUCAUAGAUAUUCCUCUGUACUGCUCAGUUGCACGUGAUCUUUUAGGGCACCAUGUUAUUGUAGACUGUCAGGCAUUUACUCUCUUCAUUGUGAGUUCCUCCUGCCUUUCCACUUGAGUGCACAUCUUGGCAAAGAUGAAAUGUCAAUUUCUGGGAAAGGCACCUAUGUGUUGUUUCCCUUAUUAUUUUUAAUUAAUUUAUUUUUUUUAAACAGAGUGGAAAUUAGAGACUUAAAAAUGAUCAAAAUACAGAAAUAUGAAAUUAUUUUUCCUGAGGUUCAGACUGGUUAAAGGAAGAUUGAAAGUUUCCAUUGUAUUUGAUAAAGGCAUGUGAAUUCUAAUCAGGUCACAGGGCAUCAAGAGGGGUCUUUAACUCUUUGGGAACAUAAAGUACACUUUUUAAAUAAAAUUAUAACUUUUCCUGGGGUGACUUUGUCAUGGGUAAAUUUGGGCCAAGGUUAAUGGUUUUAGAGGUUGAAUUACUUAUGUUUGUUUUAUGUAAAGUAAUAUAUUAGGGCAAGAGAUUUGAAUGAACAAAAUAAACAAAAGAUAUGGUCUCUAUCUUCAAAGCUUGCAUUUUAGUUAGAAAACAAAAUCUGCAUAAUGAAAUUAUAUAAACGAGUGAUCAAAUCACAUAAUAAGUACAACUUGAAAAUGAUGAUAGGUAAAUAGAAUUCAUCAAGAAAGAAUAACUGGAGACCCAGCAUUUGAAACAGAUGGGAAUAAAUUGGUUAAAAAAAAUAAAAAAAAGUGUUUAUAAUAAGUUGAAUGUAAUUUAAGGAAUCUGAAGCAUUAAAAAUCUGUGCUUAGGUGAAACUGCAGUUUAUUUACCUUUUAGAAACUAGUCUGAUUUUUUUUCCUUCUGUUGUUUGAAAAUUUACAAAUUAGGAAUUUGUCAUAGGAGAUGUAAAUAUAUUUCUAACAUGAGAAACUAAUGUCUAGAUAAUGAAAGGGCAUGGGAAGGAAGCCUUAAACAUGACAUUAUUCAGUCAGAAUAGGAUUGCAUUGAUCCAGCGGUGUGAAAAUCAUUAUGGAGUGGUGUUUUCACACAGGCCUCUUCCUUUACUUUAUUCUGAACUACAUAAAUAUCAAUUAAAGCUUUCUAGUCCAAGUUAGCAGAUGGCGAUUUAUGUCGGACUUAUAAACAAAGCCCCAGAACAUUACUAUACCUAAUUGAUGAAUGCUCUCUCCCUUUCCUGAACAAAGAUUUUGGCCUCCAGUGUGGUUGUCUGAGAGAAAAUUAAUGAAUUCUUUUCUGUGGUCUCAUGUAGAAAGGCUCCCGUUUAUAGAAAUAUUUGACUUUUUCCCCCCCAAAAAAGAAAACUUGAAUGCUUUUAAGUUGCCUAGUAAUUUAAAUUCCCAAAGAUGGACUGGAAUAGUAUUUGGCAUUAACAUUUACCUAAAAAAUUAUAUUUUCGGCUUACAGCAGAAUGAUGCCUCAAAACACAAAAUAGUAAUCAAAAUAAAGCACACAGAAAAGUGGAAUGUGUUUAAUUAUUAUAACUUUAGGUAGACAUCCAAAUUAGGGCUCAUAUUUUAUUGUUGUUUUUAAUUAUUUCUAUUUAUUAUUAUUAUUUUUUGAGAUGGAGUCUCCCUCUGUCAUCCAGGCUAGAGUGUAGGGGCCAAUCUCUGCUCACUGCAACCUCCAUCUCCUGGGAUCAAGCGAUUCUCCCGCCUCAGCCUCCCAAAUAGCUGGGAUUACAGGCCGCCGCCACCAUGGCCUGCUAAUUUUUGUACUUUUAGUAGAGAUGGGUUUUGCCAUGUUGGCCAGGCUGGUUUUGAACUCCUGACCUCAGGUGAUCCGCUUGCCUUGGCCUCCCAAAUUGCUGGGAUUACAGGCAUGAACCACUGCACCCAGCCAGAGCUCAUAUUUUAGACUCUUUUUCUGUGAACUCUUUUCUUUCGACUUGUUGUUCUUUAAGGUGAGAUGACACUUUGUACUAAUUCUUAAAAUGAACCCUUCCCUCAAUUUGAAAUAUGUGAAAAUAGCUGUUUUGUACUAUGGACCUGUAAGUGGCGUCUUGUGGUUUAGGGGCUGUUGCAAUGUCCACCUCCAGUGGAAUGUAGGUCGCUGCAUCAGAAGAAGGUAGAGGAGCCAGGCCUGUGACUGCAGAAUGUAUUCCUUACCUUUUGUUUGAAAAUAGUAAAUUUCAUUUGUGAAACAAAACCUGCCUUUUCUUUUUCAUCCUAGCUUCUUUGAAAUGAGCAGUAGGCUGAUCGGGGGUAGAUAUUCAAAUAUACUGAAACAUUAAGGUUGCUGUAGAUGAGAAAACAGUGGUACUUUGGUUGAGGGCAAUCUGCACUAAACACUUUGACUUUAAUGAUAGCUUUCUGCCCGCUGCCACCCAGGUGUCUUUCUUGUGCUCAUUGGUUUGAGGGUGCAUUCCUCAAAUGAGAGGGGCAAUUCAGGUAAAAGUUUUCAAUGUUCCUGCCCAAGGCAGCCUGCUAAAGGAAGUUCUCUUGGUGAUGACCAUCACAUGAUUGCCACGGGAAUGUGUUUACUACACGAUCUGUUGAUACAGGUAAUAAAGAACACACUGAUGACUUUUCCCCACGUAAUCUCUGAGGUCGGUAUUUUAGUAACCUUUGAGAUAAUAAUUUAACUCACGCCCUAUAGAAAUUAUGUAUGCAGUAGGCCCUUGGUAGAGACUGACAUUUAUAUAAGGUCAGUGUUGGUUGACCUAGUUUGAUCUGGCCCUAGAUUUAUAAAUGAAUGAAUGAUCUCCCCAGAAUUAGGAAGACAUGACAUCAAAAAUAUGAAUUCAUCAUUACUGUAAAAGUUUAACAUGCUGUUAAACUGUAGCAUGUUAGUGAGACGAGGCCUCAGUAUCUUCUGCUGGUUGGGGAAAAAAAAUAAAUGUGUAUUAAGUCUCAGGAGCCUGCGUGGUCCUCAUGCUUGUUAAAUCCAGAAUGGGUCUCUCCCUUUCUCCAAAGAUGGAGUUUGGCCUUGGUGGGAUUCUGUGUUGGGAGCUGCAGUCCCAGAUGCUUCUGCUAGUUUAAUAGAAGAGAUCAGGAAGAACAAACUGGCAAGUGAAUUGGACAGAUACAGACCCAAAAGACUUCAGAUAAUUGGAAAGAAAUUUUGCAACCAGGGCAUUUCUGCCAUCAAAACAGAGAGCACAAAACUUAUUGACAUGAGCCUGGAAUUUUGAAGAAGCCAGUUGAGGGAAGUUCUCCAUGAAUGUACGUCACAAUGAUGAUGACCGACCAAAUCCCUCUGGAACUGCCACCAUUGCUGAACGGAGAGGUAGCCAUGAUGCCCCACUUGGUGAAUGGAGAUGCAGCUCAGCAGGUUAUUCUCGUUCAAGUUAAUCCAGGUGAGACUUUCACAAUAAGAGCAGAGGAUGGAACACUUCAGUGCAUUCAAGGACCUGCUGAAGUUCCCAUGAUGUCACCCAAUGGAUCCAUUCCUCCCAUUCAUGUGCCUCCAGGUUAUAUCUCACAGGUGAUUGAAGAUAGUACUGGAGUCCGCCGGGUGGUGGUCACACCCCAGUCUCCUGAGUGUUAUCCCCCAAGCUACCCCUCAGCCAUGUCUCCAACCCAUCAUCUCCCUCCCUAUCUGACUCACCAUCCACAUUUUAUUCAUAACUCACACACGGCUUACUACCCACCUGUUACCGGACCUGGAGAUAUGCCGCCUCAGUUUUUUCCCCAGCAUCAUCUUCCCCACACAAUAUAUGGUGAGCAAGAAAUUAUACCAUUUUAUGGAAUGUCAACCUACAUCACCCGAGAAGACCAGUACAGCAAGCCUCCGCACAAAAAACUGAAAGACCGCCAGAUCGAUCGCCAGAACCGCCUCAACAGCCCUCCUUCUUCUAUCUACAAAAGCAGCUGCACAACAGUAUACAAUGGCUAUGGGAAGGGCCAUAGUGGUGGAAGUGGCGGAGGCGGCAGCGGUAGUGGUCCCGGAAUUAAGAAAACAGAGCGACGAGCAAGAAGCAGCCCAAAGUCGAAUGAUUCAGACUUGCAAGAAUAUGAGUUGGAAGUAAAGAGGGUGCAAGACAUUCUUUCGGGAAUAGAGAAACCACAGGUUUCUAAUAUUCAGGCAAGAGCAGUUGUGUUGUCCUGGGCUCCCCCUGUUGGACUUUCCUGUGGACCCCACAGUGGUCUUUCCUUCCCCUACAGUUACGAGGUGGCCUUAUCAGACAAAGGACGAGAUGGAAAAUACAAGAUAAUUUACAGUGGAGAAGAAUUAGAAUGUAACCUGAAAGAUCUUAGACCAGCAACAGAUUAUCAUGUGAGGGUGUAUGCCAUGUACAAUUCCGUAAAGGGAUCCUGCUCCGAGCCUGUUAGCUUCACCACCCACAGCUGUGCACCCGAGUGUCCUUUCCCCCCUAAGCUGGCACAUAGGAGCAAAAGUUCACUAACCCUGCAGUGGAAGGCACCAAUUGACAACGGUUCAAAAAUCACCAACUACCUUUUAGAGUGGGAUGAGGGAAAAAGAAAUAGUGGUUUCAGACAGUGCUUCUUCGGGAGCCAGAAGCACUGCAAGUUGACAAAGCUUUGUCCGGCAAUGGGGUACACAUUCAGGCUGGCCGCUCGAAACGACAUUGGUACCAGUGGUUAUAGCCAAGAGGUGGUGUGCUACACAUUAGGAAAUAUCCCUCAGAUGCCUUCUGCACCAAGGCUGGUUCGAGCUGGCAUCACAUGGGUCACGUUGCAGUGGAGUAAGCCAGAAGGCUGUUCACCCGAGGAAGUGAUCACCUACACCUUGGAAAUUCAGGAGGAUGAAAAUGAUAACCUUUUCCACCCAAAAUACACUGGAGAGGAUUUAACCUGUACUGUGAAAAAUCUCAAAAGAAGCACACAGUAUAAAUUCAGGCUGACUGCUUCUAAUACGGAAGGAAAAAGCUGUCCAAGCGAAGUUCUUGUUUGUACGACGAGUCCUGACAGGCCUGGACCUCCUACCAGACCGCUUGUCAAAGGCCCAGUUACAUCUCAUGGCUUUAGUGUCAAAUGGGAUCCCCCUAAGGACAAUGGUGGUUCAGAAAUCCUCAAGUACUUGCUAGAGAUUACUGAUGGAAAUUCUGAAGCGAAUCAGUGGGAAGUGGCCUACAGUGGGUCGGCUACCGAAUACACCUUCACCCACUUGAAACCAGGCACUUUGUACAAACUCCGAGCAUGCUGCAUCAGUACCGGCGGACACAGCCAGUGUUCUGAAAGUCUCCCUGUUCGCACACUAAGCAUUGCACCAGGUCAAUGUCGACCACCGAGGGUUUUGGGUAGACCAAAGCACAAAGAAGUCCACUUAGAGUGGGAUGUUCCUGCAUCGGAAAGUGGCUGUGAGGUCUCAGAGUACAGCGUGGAGAUGACGGAGCCCGAAGACGUAGCCUCGGAAGUGUACCAUGGCCCAGAGCUGGAGUGCACCGUCGGCAACCUGCUUCCUGGAACCGUGUAUCGCUUCCGGGUGAGGGCUCUGAAUGAUGGAGGGUAUGGUCCCUAUUCUGAUGUCUCAGAAAUUACCACUGCUGCAGGGCCUCCUGGACAAUGCAAAGCACCUUGUAUUUCUUGUACACCUGAUGGAUGUGUCUUAGUGGGUUGGGAGAGUCCUGAUAGUUCUGGUGCUGACAUCUCAGAGUACAGGUUGGAAUGGGGAGAAGAUGAAGAAUCCUUAGAACUCAUUUAUCAUGGGACAGACACCCGUUUUGAAAUAAGAGACCUGUUGCCUGCUGCACAGUAUUGCUGUAGACUACAGGCCUUCAAUCAAGCAGGGGCAGGGCCGUACAGUGAACUUGUCCUUUGCCAGACGCCAGCGUCUGCCCCUGACCCCGUCUCCACUCUCUGUGUCCUGGAGGAGGAGCCCCUUGAUGCCUACCCUGAUUCACCUUCUGCGUGCCUUGUACUGAACUGGGAAGAGCCGUGCAAUAACGGAUCUGAAAUCCUUGCUUACACCAUUGAUCUAGGAGACACUAGCAUUACCGUGGGCAACACCACCAUGCAUGUUAUGAAAGAUCUCCUUCCAGAAACCACCUACCGGAUCAGAAUUCAGGCUAUAAAUGAAAUUGGAGCUGGACCAUUUAGUCAGUUCAUUAAAGCAAAAACUCGGCCAUUACCACCCUUGCCUCCUAGGCUAGAAUGUGCUGCUGCUGGUCCUCAGAGCCUGAAGCUAAAAUGGGGAGACAGUAACUCCAAGACACAUGCUGCUGAGGACAUUGUGUACACACUACAGCUGGAGGACAGAAACAAGAGGUUUAUUUCAAUCUACAGAGGACCCAGCCACACCUACAAGGUCCAGAGACUGACGGAAUUCACAUGCUACUCCUUCAGAAUCCAGGCAGCAAGCGAGGCUGGAGAAGGGCCCUUCUCAGAAACCUAUACCUUCAGCACAACCAAAAGUGUCCCCCCCACCAUCAAAGCACCUCGAGUAACACAGUUAGAAGGAAAUUCAUGUGAAAUUUUAUGGGAGACGGUACCAUCAAUGAAAGGUGACCCUGUUAACUACAUUCUGCAGGUAUUGGUUGGAAGAGAAUCUGAGUACAAACAGGUGUACAAGGGAGAAGAAGCCACAUUCCAAAUCUCAGGCCUCCAGACCAACACAGACUACAGGUUCCGCGUAUGUGCGUGUCGUCGCUGUUUAGACACCUCUCAGGAGCUAAGCGGAGCCUUCAGCCCCUCUGCGGCUUUUGUAUUACAACGAAGUGAGGUCAUGCUUACAGGGGACAUGGGGAGCUUAGAUGAUCCCAAAAUGAAGAGCAUGAUGCCUACUGAUGAACAGUUUGCAGCCAUCAUUGUGCUUGGCUUUGCAACUUUGUCCAUUUUAUUUGCCUUUAUAUUACAGUACUUCUUAAUGAAGUAAACCCAACAAAACUAGAGGUAUGAAUUAAUGCUACACAUUUUAAUACACACAUUUAUUCAGAUACUCCCCUUUUUAAAGCCCUUUUGUUUUUUGAUUUAUAUACUCUGUUUUACAGAUUUAGCUAGAAAAAAAAUGUCAGUGUUUUGGUGCACCUUUUUGAAAUGCAAAACUAGGAAAAGGUUAAACUGGAUUUUUUUUUUUAAAAAAAAGAAAAAAAAAGAAGAAAAGUAUACCAGAUACCAAAAGCUAGCUUUCUUAUGUUUUCCUUUAAAUUUUCAGAUUUACCUUCAUUCUGUUUUCACUGAUGUCUUUUGCAAGCCUUUGAUUUUUUUUUUUUUGUUACAGUUUAGUAAUUUAUAUUCACCAGUCACUUCAUAUGUCUUGAACAUCUGUAUCUGUAAACAUGAAUCACCGUGUGUGUACUUACAGGGCUAGGAUUUCAGUGUUGUCAGAGUAUUACCACACAGCAACAGCAACAUACAGAAGAUAUGUUCACUCAGAUAAGACUGCCCUAAACAACCAUUUUGUCACUCAGUUAUUUAACUGUGUUUAGCUCAUUUAAAUCAAAAUGUGUACUUUAAUCUAAAAUGUUUUAAUAAUCUGUAUUUCUUAUAAUUUUAACACUAUGAGCUGCCUGUAUAAGAAAUCAAGUAACCAGAAUGCACCUAUAAAUUAUGGAGCAUUGUAGAUUUUACCACAUCAAUUCAUAGCAGUAACUUUAAGAGGGCAUUGUGCAAUAGUUAGUUGUUUUCUUGUUCAGCUAUUUUAAAGGCUGCUUUAACUUGUUUGUUUGUCUUUGUAUAUAACUACUUCUAAUCUAAUCACUAGAGUUAUUAUAUUCUGUUAUGUUUGACCAGAAUUAUAUGACAAGAACUGGUGACAGUUUAGUGCCUCUGCCCAUUGUCCAUGAUUUACACUAAUUGUGAGCAGUCUUCUUAUGUGUCAGCUCAUUAUUUUUGAAACAUUUGCCUUUAGGCUGUUCUUUGAGGUAUCAAUGAAGUGAUUGAAUUUCAAUACCUUAAUUCAGUGCACAUAAUACUAAUGUAACAGCAGAUGAAAAUUGAUAAAACCCAAAAGAGAGUCAUCUAAAUUUGUAGUUCCUAUUUCUGUGGGUUUGCCUGGCCAUGGUUGGAGAGGGAAUGGUGUUUGAUGGUAAACACAGGGUGUUUGGGGAUCAAGGAGCCUAGAUUCUCUCCCUGGAUCUGUCACUAACUUGCUGCGUGACCUGAACACGUCACUUUACCUCUCUGUGCCUCAGUUUUCCCAUGCAUGAAAAAUAAAAUAAAAUAAAACGGGGAUUCUAAUGUUUGUAAGUGCUUUGAGAUCUUUGACCAACAGGUGCUAUUGGAGUGCAAAGUGUUACUCUUACGUGUUUAUUUUGAGUCAUGAGAUAAUCAAUUUUAACCCAAAGUCAUUGGAUUAUUUAUAUGAAGUCCAUAAUGUUCGAGUACCUCAGGGACAUUUAAGAGUUGGAGGUGCAAAUAUAUUCCAAAAGGGUGCAACAGACACAGUGUAUCCCCCUGCUUCUGUUUUUGUAUAUUUUUGCUACUUGGUUUUUCUUGAUCAUAGCUAUUUUGUGCUUGAUCUUUAUUGUCUAAGAUGCAGUAUCCUGUACUAGCUUAUAAUAUUCCCAUACCAAAGUCAUGGGGAAACAAACAUUAUUUUGUUUUUGGUUUAUUUAUACUAUAUUCUGCAUACAGUACUUUAAAUGCCAAUUACAGUGCAAUCUUUAUUUAUUGUAAAAUUUUUUAAGUGUACUUAUGUACUAAUUUUCCCUUGUAGCAUGUUAUAUUUUUGUGUUUUAUACUUUUGUAAUUUUAGGUCAGUCUUGUUCCUUGGCAACAUCUGUAGUAUUAUUAAUCUUCUGACAUUUUCUUAUGUUUUUAAAAAGAUAAGAGCAUCUAGUGCAUUAAAUGCCAAAAAAAAAAUACAUUAUCAGUGAUUGAAACGUUUACAUGUACCCAAAAACCAUAAUCAUCUCUUGGAAGAAAAUGCUGAGAUCAAUGAAUUAUUCUGUGUGCCUAUAUUGACGUAGUGAGUACUAGAGAGUUCUGUAUUUUAUUAUUGACUAUAAUAAUUAGUUUAAUUAGCUUUGCAAACUGAUGGCAUCAAGGUAAAUAUAUUUUUGCCAAAGUUCUGGCCUUCCAAAACUCACCCCCUUAUUUAAAUGUGUGCUAUGACCCACUAUGACCACAGCAUCUGCAUUUUCUAAAAAAUUCCAUGCAGGUGUUUUGGGGAGAGGUAUUUUUUAAGCAAUGAAAAUUCAACUGAGUACAAAGCCCCCUCUUGGGGGGUUGGGGAAGUCUCUUUUUUGAAACACUUCAGAACUGCUGCUAUAAAGAAAUUCUCUAAUUGGUUGAAUUUUUUUUUUAAGUAAAUAGUACUUUAGGCCAAAAUUUAUAUGAAUAUUUGAUCUUCUUGAGAUUUUCAUACUAUCAUUUAACCACCAGGAAGCUGAAGUGUGUGAAGUACAAAGCUGACAGCACUUUAUUUUAUUGCUCUCCAUUAUUUGGUAUUCAUUAUAUUCCUUCAGUCAGAAAAUUAUUACUCUCUAUGGCACUGUUUUUUAUCACAAAUAUGUAUAUGUGAUAUUGAUAUAUAACUAUAUAUAUUGCCAUCACACACGAACAAUAAAAUAAAGUGUUCUAUUAACCUGAUCUCUUUGCCCUUUUGCUAUGUGAGGAGUGAAUGAGUGGCCUUCUGAUGCUCUGACUCUUCUCUGUAUGUCAAACUCAUCCCUGGCACAAGAAAUUCCAGUCAUGUGAAGCAAACUGCCCUUUGUCCUCAAAGAAAUUGUUGAAAAAGAAAACUUUUUAAAGAGAUUUUUUGCAUAUUCUCUGCCUUGUUCUUAUCAACUUGAAAUGUUGGCAUUUUCUAACCUUGUUUUGUUGGCUACAAUAAUUCAGUAUUCAUGUCAAAAUUGAGAAGUGCCCUAAUUGAAUGUGUUUGAAUGUUAUCCUUGCACAAUUCUUUAAAUUGAAAGAUAAAAUGUUUUACCUCACUGUUGGACAUACAUUCCAAGCUUUUCAACUCUAGGAGAAAAAGAAAAUCAUGUUUUCCUGUAUUGUAAAUUUUAGACUAUUUCAUAUACAUUGUAUUAAAACUGCCAUAUCAAUUUUAAUGUAUAGAUUUUGCAAAUAUUAUGCUAUAUGUAAUACCUAACUGUAUCUGUAGUGUAUAUGUAAUAUAUUUAUGCCCAAUAAAUGUUUUAAUUCUUUCUGACUUAAAUAGGGUUUUUCUGCCAUGACUAGGAUUGCUUUUGUUGUUGUUGUUGUUGUUUCUUUCUUUUUUUUUUUUUUUGAGACGGAGUCUUGCUCUGUCGCCAGGCUGGAGUGCAGUGGCGCGAUCUCAGCUCACUGCAACCUCCAGCUCCCAGGUUCAAGUGAUUCCCCUGCCUCAGCCUCCCAAGUAGCUGGGGAUUACAGGCACUCGCCACCAUGCCCGGAUAAUUUUUUUUUUUUUUUUGAGUUGGAGUCUUGCUCUGUCGCCCAGGCUGGAGUGCAGUGACCCAAUCUCGGCUCACUGCAAGCUCCACCUCCCGGGUUCAUGCCAUUCUCCUGCCUCAGCCUCCCAAGUAGCUGGGACUACAGGUGCCCGCCACCACGCCCGGCUAAUUUUUUUAAUUUUAGUAGAGUCGGGGUUUCACCAUGUUGGCCAAGAUGGUCUCGAUCUGACCUCGUGAUCUGCCCGCCUCGGCCUCCCAAAGUGCUGGGAUUACAGGUGUGAGCCCCCGCACCCAGCCUUAUUCUUCCCUUUUAAAUACUUAAAGCACAUUCAGAUUAGUUGAAAAUUCACGUGUUUUUGGAGGCCAGGCAGGUGGCCUUCUGCAGAGACAGCAGCAGCUCAGCUCUUGCUGACCAAGGCCUUGGAGGACUGUGAGCCACAAUCACAUAUGUCCAUGUUUCAAAAGAAGCUAAAUAUCCAGAUUUCCUCCAUGGGCCAACUAAAAGGUGAUUGUGGACUAUACAGGCUGCCAGUUUAAUCCUUUAUCAGAGUCUCUGUGGAUAAUGUACCUUGUUGCCUAAUACUUUAUCUGUCUACCAAAACUCAGUCCAGAUCUCCCUCUGUUCACCUGGCACACUGGGUGCUUCCUCUCCCCUGACGAACUCUAUAGAGUGUUCAUGUCCUUUCCUGCAGGUCUCAUUCAACAACAACAACAACAACAGCAAUAAAACACAGUGUUCCUGCUAUGGC